AGCAGCUGCUGCCAGCCCGCGGGCACUGAAGUCCUCCCGGCUGCCGCUCGAGUAGCCACGGGCGCGAUCGGGACCAGAAGUCUCCUCCUCCAUGAUCACUUUGGAAGCCGGGGGAAGACUUUGCCCUGCCCUGAGAGCUGGUCUGCGUUUCCCAGGCGCGGCGGCGGCGGAGCAGCAGCUGCAGCAGCCGAGUCCAAAUAGGAGCGGCCACAGCCAGGGGCGUGAGCGCCCCGCGCGGAGCGAGCUCGGGUUCCCCUCGGAAUGUCCCCGGGGCGCCCGGCGCGCUGACCCCGAAGCCGCCUCCGCCUUCGGCGCCUGCUGCCUCCCUCGGCCAGGCUUGUUGUUCGGGACUGUGAGCUUCCUGGCUCCUGGGCAGUGGGGAAGCCCCCGGGGGCGAGUGACUUCAGCUGGCCACGACCCAGCCCUCCCCCGUGCGUAUCUCGCUUAAGAUGGCAGCGGAGUCAGGGGAACUAAUCGGGGCUUGUGAGUUCAUGAAAGAUCGGUUAUAUUUUGCUACUUUAAGGAAUAGACCAAAAAGCACAGUAAAUACCCACUAUUUCUCCAUCGAUGAGGAGCUGGUCUAUGAAAAUUUCUAUGCAGAUUUUGGACCGCUGAACUUGGCAAUGGUGUACAGAUAUUGCUGCAAACUAAACAAGAAACUAAAAUCAUACAGUUUGUCAAGAAAGAAAAUAGUGCACUACACCUGUUUUGACCAACGGAAAAGAGCAAAUGCAGCAUUUUUGAUAGGUGCCUAUGCAGUAAUCUAUUUAAAGAAGACACCAGAAGAAGCCUACAGAGCACUCCUGUCUGGCUCAAACCCCCCCUAUCUUCCAUUCAGGGAUGCUUCCUUUGGAAAUUGCACUUACAAUCUCACCAUUCUCGACUGUUUGCAGGGAAUCAGAAAGGGAUUACAACAUGGAUUUUUUGACUUUGAGACAUUUGAUGUGGAUGAAUAUGAACAUUAUGAGCGAGUUGAAAAUGGUGACUUCAACUGGAUUGUUCCAGGAAAAUUUUUAGCAUUUAGUGGACCACAUCCUAAAAGCAAAAUUGAGAAUGGUUAUCCUCUUCACGCCCCUGAAGCCUACUUUCCUUAUUUCAAAAAGCAUAAUGUGACUGCAGUUGUGAGGCUAAACAAAAAGAUUUAUGAGGCAAAGCGCUUCACAGACGCUGGCUUCGAGCACUAUGACCUCUUCUUCAUAGAUGGCAGCACACCCAGUGACAACAUCGUGCGAAGGUUCCUGAACAUCUGUGAGAACACCGAAGGGGCCAUCGCCGUUCACUGCAAAGCUGGUCUUGGAAGAACAGGGACAUUGAUAGCCUGUUAUGUAAUGAAACACUACAGGUUUACACAUGCUGAAAUAAUUGCUUGGAUUAGAAUAUGCCGGCCAGGCUCUAUUAUAGGACCCCAGCAGCACUUCCUGGAAGAAAAACAAGCAUCGUUGUGGGUCCAAGGAGACAUUUUCCGAUCCAAACUGAAAAAUCGACCAUCCAGUGAAGGAAGUAUUAAUAAAAUUCUUUCUGGCCUAGAUGAUAUGUCUAUUGGUGGAAAUCUUUCAAAAACACAAAACAUGGAACGAUUUGGAGAGGAUAACUUAGAAGAUGAUGAUGUGGAAAUGAAAAAUGGUAUAACCCAGGGAGACAAACUACGUGCCUUAAAAAGUCAGAGACAGCCACGUACCUCACCAUCCUGUGCAUUUAGGUCAGAUGAUACAAAAGGACAUCCAAGAGCAGUGUCCCAGCCUUUCAGAUUAAGUUCAUCCCUGCAAGGAUCUGCAGUUACUUUGAAGACAUCAAAAAUGGCACUGUCCCCUUCAGCAACGGCCAAGAGGAUCAACAGAACUUCUUUGUCUUCGGGUGCCACUGUAAGAAGCUUUUCCAUAAACUCCCGGCUAGCCAGUUCUCUAGGGAACUUGAAUGCUGCAACAGAUGAUCCAGAGAACAAAAAGACCUCCUCAUCCUCUAAGGCAGGCUUCACAGCCAGCCCGUUUACCAACCUCUUGAAUGGCAGCUCCCAGCCAACUACCAGAAAUUACCCUGAGCUCAACAAUAAUCAGUACAACAGAAGCAGCAACAGCAACGGGGGCAACCUGAACAGCCCCCCAGGCCCCCACAGCGCCAAGACAGAGGAGCACACCACCAUCCUCCGACCCUCCUACACCGGGCUUUCUUCUUCUUCAGCGAGAUUCCUGAGCCGUUCUAUCCCUUGUUCAUGCCUACUGCUAGUCUUUAGGAAGCCCUUUCUUGGAAGCCCCCUGCUCUCCUUACCAAUUUCUCAUCUUUAAAUAAAGACAUAUAUUACCUCCCAUGUCUUCUGUGAAGCUCUCCCCAUCCCUUCAGUCUGAAUAUGUUCAUUACUAAGGCCUUGCCACUCCAGUGAAAGCUGUUCUUCUCUUAGACACAAUUUCUUCAUCUGGACGAGCAGUGGAGAGGGAAAGCAACUUCUUGCUGGAAGAAUAUCUCUGCCUUCUUACCUUAAAUUAAAAAGAGCACUAAGAUAACACCUUCAAGAGACUUGAAAACAGAAAACUGGUUAAUGACUACUAUAAAUGCACUGAAACUAUGUUUAUGGAGAUUUCCAUACUUUUAAAGACAGUUUUAAUGUUGAAUUUGGUAUUUUGAAGGGUUAUUUUUAAUGUAUUUUGGUAAUACAUUUAUUAUUAUAUUUACAUGUACAGUGUUACAUUAUAUAUGUAUUGUGAACUUUAAAAGACUAUUUUGAUAAAUUUAUAAAUAUAUAAAAUUAUGUAAAAACUACACUAUAUUUUGAUUUAGAUUUUCCUGCUGUUUGCUACCAAAAAUUUGUAUUUUAAAUCUGUUUAGUUUUAGUAUGGUUUUGUCUCUAAUGAAUAAAUAAUUCCUUCUUAUUAAGAAGAAGUAAGGGAGAAAGUUUUUAGAAAGUGAUUUUUAUGCUCGCACUAUAAAUAUGGCAGGUCAGUUCAUUCUUUUGGGAAGUCAGUUUAGUUACACUGAGUUUAUCCAAGUUUAUCUCUACCAAGAGUAUAAUGGCAUGGGAUGGCUUAUUUAGGACAAUUCCCUUUCCUAUUGUUUUUGUUGCUGAGCCAAUUUGAGUUAGUUUUGCAUCCUGGGGGGCUUUAAAAUACAGCAUGCAGUGAAAGAUCAGAAUUCACUGAAUAUUUCUUCUGAGAGCAUGGUUUCAUGGUUUUUCUCUAUGAAAUGACUCAAUAUUCCAAAUGUUUUUUUUUCCUUCCUCCUUUCAAAAGAGUUCUUAACCCAAUUAGGAUAUCCUGCUUUGGGUAUGAGGUUGUUGUUGCCUGUAAUCACACAUGGUUUGACAUCAGUUUUAAAUCAAUGGAGAGAAAAAACUGAAAAAGAUGCUGCUAAGUAGUUCUCUGUAUUAAAGGAGAUAUUUUUAAAACAGGGUACAACCCCCUGCUGCACACGCUAGCAUAUCUGGAACCUACUAUGAAAAUGAAAGGACCCUUAUAGGUACUCACAGCCCUUUCAUGUAAGUAUGAUCUGAUAUUUAGGUCUUCAGAAGCCUGUAGGUUUCAUUUCUAUGAGGAAUCGAGGAGCGUUACAUCCUGAUAUCCUUCCAGGCUGCUUAAGAAUGGACUGCUUCGACACUGAAAGUGCUAGUUAAAUGGAUUCAUAUGAAGUGCUUUACUCCCAACCAUUGAGUUAUUUAUAAUGUAUUUAUUAGGGGAGGGUACCUUGAGUCUAUUAUAUAUGCUUCAUCAAAACAUCUUGUUCAUGUUUUAUGUUUUUAAAAAAGGCAUUUGAAUGAAUGUUUGACUCAGGUUUGUUAAAUUAACCUUCAGUAACUGCAGUACCAAAAAUUACACUCAACUGAUGAAAAAAACGAAUUGUAUGAUUUAGGAAUCAAAAACUAAAAUAAGUGGAAUUAUGUAUCUUUUCUAAAGUUAAAAAAGUAAAAUAUUUUAUUAUGAGUUAUUAUAAAAAUUGGUUAAUUGUAUAGGAAGAUGACAGUAUUUUUUUCAAGUUAUCAUAAAAAGUAAUUCAGAUGACAUUUGAGAAGUAGGGGAAAGGGAAUCAUGUUGACAGUUUUAGUUCUGUGAACACUAAUUUGUGUGAAGCUAUUAAAAUGAUUGUAAAGUUGACUACUGUAAAUUUCCCAUAAUUAUGUGUGUAUAUGUGUCAUAUGUAUGUACAUGUAUAUGUCUAAAAAUUACUUUACACAUGUGCCUACAUAGACACACCAAGAAGUGGAUGUAUAUAAUAUAGAAAGUAUAUAGCAAAGUAAUUUUACUCUGAUAAUAAAAAUUGUUUGACAUGUAUUUUGUUAUGAAUAGUUUAUCUUCCAAAAGAUAUUUUGCUCUAUUUUAAAGUGUAGAAGAAUACACUGCUAAUAAAUAAUAAAAGUUUUAUUCAAUUUA